GGGGCGCACGCUGGCGGCGCGGUCGCUUUAAGGAGGCGCCGGGGCGGGGACGGACCGGAGUGGCCGGCUGGCGGGGAGCCGUCAGUCCGGCGGCCGCGGGGCCCGGCGGGCGCGACGCUGCCUCCUCACCGGCGCAGGCUAGGAGGGGGCGGCCUGAGUGCCGUAGCCGAGCCGGGGCUGGAGCGCGCGGUGAGUGGUCGGGCGGCCUUGGAGGGGAGGGGGCCCGGCCGCGCCGCCUCUCGCCCCGGCCGUCGCUUUGUUCCGGGGCGGGAGGUGUGGCCGCCCUCCGGGCUCGGCCGCGCUCUCCGCUUGCGGGGUGCGCCCUGGGACCGGCUGUGCGUGGCGUUUUGCCCCCAUCGCGGGCUCCCGCGUAACGGUGUGCGUUCGUGAAAUCGGCCACGACCAAGACCCCAGUGGGGAGGGCCUGCGCGCCGCUCAGAGAGACCCUUUCAUGCCUGCUUCAUAAACAACCCUUCACUGCCCCCGGAGGUUUGGGGAGCUGGAGCUGUGGUCACAACUAGGGCCUGGGCUCAUGCAUUGAACUGAUCUGGCUGAGGCAUCAGACACGGUGCCAGUCCUGCCCUGCGGGGAAGACAAGAGCACAAAGUGACAAGCCAGUGUGGACUCACUCUGUCCUGGACCUGACCAGAGAGGGUGGCUGACAAGGCUCGGAAUCGUGGCCUCCAGAGGUUUGUCUGGCAGCAGAAGUAAGAUGGAGAUAUGACUUUAAGAGCUCUGAAACUCCACUGUAAUAACAGCAACCAACAGGGCUUCCAAAGACCAGGCACUUGAAGUGGAUUUGCUCAUCAUUUGACAAGACACCUCUUGACAAGACACCUCCAGAAGGAUUUUGUUUAUUGUAAAGGAUGGAGGAACUGGGGUGAAAAAGAGCCAACAGCUUGCCCAAGAUCAUAUCUGAAGUCCAUGCUUUUGGCCACGUGGCUGUCCUGGGCUUCGGAAGGCUCUGGUGCAGCCUGUGUUAGAGUUUUGUAAUAUAUUGUUUUAUAAUUAUUCACUAUAGACAUUCACUGGUGGGUUGAAGUGUGAGGCAGUGAGCUGUGGGUAUUAAUAACUGACUCGUGUCAGAAGCUUAGCAGUGAACAAAGCACUUUCUCGGAUACGGUUCUUAGAGCUUCUCCUGCUUCUUUUCCCGGGGAAGAAACUUGAGCUGCUAACAUUUUGUAAACCUCCUAAUUUCCUGUAAAUCACAUGUCCCUGCUGAGUGGGGCUGAAAAUGUUUCGGGCAAUGGUUUUCACCCUUAGGUCUGUUCACACUGCCCAGCAGCCAGUUAGCUUCUCUCUGUAGUUUAUGGUGUAGUUUGUCCUUUUUCUGCCGGGGUGGGAGGCAUGGGGCUUUCAUGCUCUGGGGUUUUUGAGGUCUGCCAGCCUCUGGGGAGGGAGGUGUUGGGCAAGCCUCGUGCUCUGGUGGAAACUGACCCCCUAGAUGUGACCUCGGCAUUUCCUAAAGCUGGGGGCGGGACUGGGGUAGGCGGUAGUCAAGGCCCUUUGGUGAAGCAAGCGAUUGUCUCCAGCGUUGUCAGCUUCGCUCCUCCAUAAGACAGUUGCUAAUUUCCACCUCUGUUUUCACCUACAUAAGACACUUUAUGACAGGUUUAACUUUUAUGUUAUUAUUAGCUCUAGCCACUGGUAUUUCAUACUCAGUUCGUCUGAGCUACUUAUAAAGUGACAAGUCCAGCCAGGGCAACAUGGUGAAACUCCGUCUCUACAAAAAUUAGCUGGGCCUGGUGGCAUGCACCUGUAGUCUUAGCUACUUGGGAGGCUGAGGUGGGAGGAUUGCUUAAGCCCAGAAGGCAGAGGUUGGAGUGAGCCAUGAUCACGCCACUGCACUCCAGCUUGGGUGACAGAGCAAGACCCUGUCUCAAAAAAAAAAAAAAAAAAAAAAGUGACAAGUCAGUUACCCUUGGGGUUGGUUUGGUUCCUAAGCUCUAGUGAUCACCUGGAACCAGGAAUGACUAUUGGCCUCUGAUAAAUUAGGCUCCUGGGAUGACUGGUCCUAACCUCAGUCAGAAUCACAUGUUGACCAGCCUCCUGGAUCUAGUGAGUUCUCAGGGAAAUGUGGCUUCCAUAAUAUAUUUCACAUCAGAUUUAACCAUUGUAAUCUGUUCUGCCAAUGAAAUGCCCCCAAACAGAGUGUGUCUCCCUGAAAGCAAUUGAAAAACAUACCUGCUCAUGAGCAUUGUGUAGUUUGUACAAGCAUACUCAUGUGAACUGAAUGGGAAUGCAUUCUUGUGCAAUGCUGGAAUGUUCUUAAGUGUCCAGAGGAUGUGCAUUGAGUUCCAGAGGCUCUGUACCUGCCAGGCCCUGGGCAGGCAUAGAAGGUACAGUCACCUUUAUCUGGAGACAGGUAAAAAAGGAGCUGGAGGAGUUCCCUGAGACCUGGGACACCUGGCAGGUACCCAUUGUCUAGGGACUCAGCAGAGAAUUCAAGCUUUAAGAGGAAUUUUCUUGCUGGACUCUGAGUCCCUGUCAGCCCUCCUAAGUCUUAGAUCAUGCCUCUGAGCCCUGUAGUACUGAAUCAAUGGGGAUGCUUUGGCUGCAAGUAACAAAACCCAAAUAACAGUAAGUAAGAUUAAGCAGAGCUCAGAUCUCCCAAAGAUGCUCUCUGCUCUUGGAAGGUCUCUGUACACAGGAAUGGGAUAUCAGUGCCACUUCCAGCAAGUUCCUGCAUGGGACAGGUAGCCAUAAAGGCUGAGUGUCUGGAGUUCAGAGUAAUAGGUUUUGUCUUCUUGAGUCACAGCCUCUUUAAUAUGUUGAUGAGAAGCCCAGGGAACGUUGAUGUACAAAGUUGGACAUAUAAUUCAGGGGAUUCAUGGAUCUCUGAAAACCAGCCCUGGAUCCCAGUUUAGCCAUCUCUGAUCUAAAGGCACGUGACUUCUCUAAUGUUCAUGGCAGACCUAUUCUGUAAGCCCAUUGUGCAGCCAAGUCAGCAUGCCAUUCCAGUGCAGUGUGAGAGGGCAGAGAUGGGGGCCAAGAGUACAAAUAGAGUGGGACAGUUGUCAUUGCCCAGCCUGUGAGUUGAAGUCUGUGCAGUCAGCCAGUGGGUCUGACAAAGAGGGCAGUGCUGGCACUGCCUCAUGCUUCCGCAGAGGUGAUGAGGUUCAGGCUGAGGUGGAGACCACGCUGCACUCGCCAUGCAUUCAAUGGUGCCCCAUCUCUUGUUCUCUAGGAAGCAUUCCCGCUACCUGUGUGAUGCAGUUGGUUCCACCUAUUCCCAGAGACUCCACCCUGGCCCUCCUUGCCCUGGCCCCCAGCACUGAGCCCCUAGGGCCAUUUAGCUGGCCAGCAUGAUCUAAGACAGCUUUCUGCAGGCAUUCCUCUUGUAGGAGUCAUGAAGCAGCAAUGUGUAUUUUGCUUCUUUUUGUUGUUGUUAUAUUAAAAAAUAUUUUUAUAUUCUAGUCCAAUCCUUAUUAUUUGAUUUUUUUGGUUAUAUGUUAUAUAUAAAAAUGUAUUUUUUGUAUUUUGCUUCUUAAUGUCCCUAUCAUUGUCUUUAAUAUUCUUGGUAGCUUCACUAGGUGGGGACUGCUGCAUGACAAUGUGGGUCAUCACCGGUUGCUGAAGUGACCUUCUGAGUCUCAGAGGGGUAUAGUCCUCGCAUCAGGCUACCUUGACGGAUAAAACAAUAUGAUUUACAUAUGGGUUGUAGUGCUAGUAAGAUUUUGGAGAGCACCAAUAAUGAAUUCGGCUGUGCAGCUUGUAGUGGCCAAGCAAAGGAGGGUGGGUGGAGAGUUGGGAGCUCUGGUUCUGGCCUCUGUGACCAUCUGUAGGGCCUUGUCUGGAUCCUGUGCUGCCUGGGCCCAGGCUGCAUCUGUGACUUCUCUGCCCAGCCCUCAGUGUCGUCAUGGGGAUUAGAUAAAAUAUACACGUGAAAAUACGCUUGGGAGGCCAGAAAGGGCUGGAAGAAUGAAGACCACUACCAGUAUUCAAGCAACCUUCGGAGGACAGAAUCCUAGACCCAGAAGGAGCCCCCUGAGUGUAUUAAGUCGAGUCACACCCCGUAGAGCACAUUUCUCAUAGUGGUGAGGAAGAUGAUUUUAGGUGGGACACAGCAUCUUUCAUUUUAAUAGUUAUAUGCUGGUUUAUUUGAAUGUAUUAUAAAAAUACAGGCAUCAGAACAAACUGGGAGUUUUUUAAUGGAUAUUUUGCCCAGAUUAAGGCUAAAGAAGUAUUUUAAGUAAAAAAAAAGAAAAUUUUUAAAAGUAUGGUGGUUUUCAGAUUAAGCUAGUUAUAGUACAAUAGUAGACAAAUAUGGCCCAAAUGGGAAAGUGAGCCCUUGAGGAAAGGCUGGGAAACUUUCCACAAGGGGAGUCCUUCCUUCCCUGACAGCCCAUUAGGGGUGUGUCUUUGACUUCACCUGGACCCUUCUAGAGACACAGUGUCUCUACCCUUUGAGUCAGUCCACUGCAUUUGCGGAUUCUCUCAUUGUUGGGAAGUUCUUUCCCUUCUUCCCUUAACCUGUCCCACAUGAACCUUUGACAGUCCUGCUUUUCUCCACCAUGAGCAGCUUUACUUUCUUCAACUGCUCUUCAAAUGUCAUAGUUUAAAAACAGCCCCUCUGUAUGUCCGUCCUUUCUUCCAUCCAUCCUUGCAGCCACCCACCUACCCGUCCAUUCAUUGAUCCAUCUCUCCAUCCAUCUUUCCUUCAGCAAAGACUUGUGGGCUGGACCCUGUACUGUAUACUUUAUAUUCGCUAUCUCUAAGCCUCACAAAAAUUGUGUUAGAUGUAGUUAACCUUUUAUAGAUGUGGAAACCGAGGCUCAAGGAAGUUAAGUAGGUCACCUGCAGUCAUAACCUGAGAGAAGCAGAGUCAGAAAGGAAUCUGGCCAUGGUCUGUCUCUUCCUGAAGUGCAUGCUCCUUCCGUUAGACCGUGCUGUUCCCAGCACUGGGUGACCAAAAAUGUCAUGAUCCCUUCUCUCCUGGUGCUUAGGGGACCUAUCCCAUGGAGGUGUGGCUCUACAUAAUCAGUGCAGUGGGCAAAGGCCUCAUGAGGAGCAGGGAUGGAGCAGCCUGUGCACAAAGAUGUGGUGAGGCAGCAGAGGUGCAGAAGACGCUGGCUGGCAAAGAGAGGCAGCGAGUCCCUCGCUGGCAGGAGUCUUCCCUGACUGUCAUUAAUCUUACAGUCACAAAUGAACCCCUAAAUCAUUUGUGCACUUUUUUUUUUAAUUUUGAAAAAGAAAAGUGUAAAGGGUAGUAUAACAAAUACCAUGUACCUAUUACCCAAGAUGAACAGAUGUGACCAUUUUGUCUGCACUUGAUCCUUUUCACAGUAGGGCUGGACUUAAAACCAGACCACUCAUCCUUUGCCCUGGCCAGUUUGGCCCAUCCUCAGCCUGCAAUGGGCUUUUGGGAGCCUUGCUCCUGAGUUUUCAUGUAUUGGCUCUCUCUUGGGGCUUCAUGUCCUCAGUUAAUGCCAGUGGGCCUCCCUAGAAGUUGUUGACUAAAGAGGCUUUUGCUGCUUCUGACCACAUUGUGGAGAAGCCACUCUGGGGAGAGUGUGUGUUUUUGGCUAUGAUCUUUUUCAGAGAAGUUCAUCUACCCUCACAAACACCUGCCUUGACCAUUGUGGGUUUAGCCAAGCUGUAGAGCAUGGUUUAGUCAUAGCUGCCUAAACUGAACUGUAAUAUUAAUGAUAGGUUUGUAUGUUUGGAAGACAGAGAAAACAUAUUCUCUUUUUAUAAUUAUAUGACAAUGAUAACAAAAUGCUUUUUGUUGUUGUUAGCAGUGAAGUCUCACUCUGUUGCUUAGGUUGGAGUGUGGUGGAGCAAUCAUAGCUUAUCACAGCCUCGAACUCCUGGGCUCAAGCCAUCCUCCUGCCUCAGCCUCCUCAGUAGCUGAGACUAUAGGCAUGUGCCACCAUGCCCAUCUAAUUUAAAAAAAUUUUUUUUGUAGAGAUGGGGUCUCCCUUUGUUGUUCAGGCUCAUCUUGAACUCCUGGUGUCAAGCGAUCCUCCCACCUCGACCUCCCAAAGUGCUGGGAUUAUAGGCAUGAGCCCCCACACCUGGACACAAAAUACAUUAUAUACUCUAAAGUAUAGGAUUACUUUAAGAGAAGGAAACUAAAAGUAUGAUGGCUUACUUUGUAAUCCAUAACUUCACAGUUUUCCCUUCCUGCAGCUUUCACAGAAAAAACCAGGUGCCUGGUACUGGGUCCUUCUCUCUGCCAAGCAGGAGUAAGGCGGCAGAGCCAACCCUGCAUCUGCAGUUAGAAGCUCUCCAUGACGACAGGACGCAGCUUCUCACCCAACUGUUUGCAGCCUUCUCCUUUCCACCUACUGAUUGACUCCUGAGCUGAAGCCUGGUGUUAUCCUGUUUGCAUGUAGUUUGCCAUGAGUUAGAACAGUCUGACCUACGAGAAACAUGGCAACCAGCGCCGUCCCCAGUGACAACCUCCCCACAUACAAGCUGGUGGUGGUGGGGGAUGGGGGUGUGGGCAAAAGUGCCCUCACCAUCCAGUUUUUCCAGAAGAUCUUUGUGCCUGACUAUGACCCCACCAUUGAAGACUCCUACCUGAAACAUACGGAGAUUGACAAUCAAUGGGCCAUCUUGGACGUUCUGGACACAGCUGGGCAGGAGGAAUUCAGCGCCAUGCGGGAGCAAUACAUGCGCACGGGGGAUGGCUUCCUCAUCGUCUACUCCGUCACUGACAAGGCCAGCUUUGAGCACGUGGACCGCUUCCACCAGCUUAUCCUGCGCGUCAAAGACAGGGAGUCAUUCCCGAUGAUCCUCGUGGCCAACAAGGUCGAUUUGAUGCACUUGAGGAAGAUCACCAGGGAGCAAGGAAAAGAAAUGGCGACCAAACACAAUAUUCCGUACAUAGAAACCAGUGCCAAGGACCCACCUCUCAAUGUCGACAAAGCCUUCCAUGACCUCGUUAGAGUAAUUAGGCAACAGAUUCCGGAAAAAAGCCAGAAGAAGAAGAAGAAAACCAAAUGGCGGGGAGACCGGGCCACAGGCACCCACAAACUGCAAUGUGUGAUCUUGUGACAGGCCUGAGGCCCUGGGCACAGUGACGGUGGCCUGGCCAGCCCUCGGGACCCCUCCCCACCUAACUGCACUGAAACCAUUUCUAACCACAACCCUUGGCCCAAGGACUUGGUACAGGAAGGGAGAAGGGCAGGUGGGCAGGGAGCAGACAGGGUCUGGCUUUGCCCAGAGGGCACGGGCUUUCCCACCUCUCAAAGAGACAAGGAAGCCACCUGUAAGCAGAAGCAGCAUCCAAGUGCCCCUGGCCCCCCCAUGUGUUGAUUCAACCCGGUUCCUCCCCCUCUCUCGGUGGGUGUGUUGUUUAUUGUAACUACAUAGUGUUGGUUUGAUGUGGAAGUGUUUAUCCACAUACAAAGUACAAAACAAGCCAUGAACAAGCUUCUUUCCCUUACCCCCCAUCCACAAUGUCUGAGCUUGGAUGUCUUUUAUAGAUUUUUAAAUUAUUUUAGUGAUUAUUAUUUUAUUAAAGGGGUCUGGGCUCACUGCCUGGUGAAGUUUCAAGUGUUCAGCAGACCUCUCUGGUAACAUAUCUGGAAUAUUGUUGUUGUUUUUUAACCGAGUUUUCCCAUCAGUGCCAAAACUCAACUCAAUCUGAAAGUAGAGUGUCUGAGAGGACAGAAGGUAAUGGGAACUGUAGCUGGAGGCCUCAGGCCAUGGGUCAAACCUGGGAGGGAAAGAGACCCUACACAUGGCCUAGAAAUGAGAGAAGAGAGAGGUAUUUACCCAGAGGAUUUUCCUAUGGUUGGGGAUGCAAAUAUUAGAAAACAGAUUGUAUUUUGCUGAGGGGAGUGGCUGUCAUGAGCAUGUCAGUUCUAAAAGGGGUUUUCAUUAUCCUGGAAAUGUAUAAACUAAAGUAAGCUGAUUGGCUUUGCAAACAUGUUCAUUUGUUUUUCAGACAGUAUGGGUUAAGUUCUCUGCCCUCCCCAGGGGUCUGAGGAGGCUCUGGGUUUCUCAGAUCUGUCUCUUGCUGCGUUUUCACAUCAGCUGUGCUGCUUGGUGCCUCUCUGAUACGAAUACACUGACACGUCAAAGUAACCUAAUGUGGACACCAUCCAGAAAACUCCAGUUCAUGCUGGAUCUUAACCAAAAAUGAUUCAAUACUGUUAUCACUAAAACAGCACCAAGACCUGAAGCCAUCUUCCCUUGGAGUCAACUGACUACCACCUCUAUAAGCCUAGUCAAUGAGCAGACCCCUUCCAGUAUUUGUAAAAGUAGUACUAGGUUGCCUUUUUGGCAAUUUUUAUUGACCUGUUGAAUCUUGACUAUAAAAUGAUCUGAGAAGUAAGGAAGGCUGGGCUGAUGUGUGGCUCUCAUAUACCUUCUGCAAGGGGGCAGUCUCCCCAGCUCCCUGAUGAUGCUCACCCCCGCCCCCCCACCUCAGGUGCUGCUGGUGUGAGCCAAAGACUGGAGUUUUUCCAGCUGGGGUGGGAGUGGAGAGACAACAGGAACAACGCUGCACCAAAGAAAAGGUCAGAAUAAAAGGCAGCACAGCUGGUGACCUUAUUUUCUAGAUGUUACAAAUCAGGUCACUAUGCAAACUAGAAUAUCCUCAGCAGGUGGCCUGGCCACUCUGGAGAAAGAAACCCAAGGAAAGUGAGCACCCAACUGGAUGCCAAGACACCCGGGUUCUGAAAAUGUGCUGUGUUCCUACCUCGGCAAGAUCACCAGCACUGAGGGGCCCAGCUGGAGAAUGAUUCUGCUACAAAAGGAGACAGUUGAGACUUUUGCUUGUUGGAAAUCAAACUUCUUAUUUGUCUAAAUUGCCCCUUUUUCUGUUCCUAAAAGGAAGGAUAAGAGAGAACAUUCCAGGUGAGGCACUUCAAAGUUUCCUUAGACCCUAUAGUGUUAAGAGGUAUUUUAAACACUAAAAGGACAAAGCUCUUCCCAAUCCUUAUGCUUCCCUAAGUGGUAUCUGCAGCAGUUUGUUGUGUGCAGUUUGAUGGCAGCUGCAAACUGGAGGUGAGGCGGAGGAAAGGCAGGUAGGAAGGAGUAAGGAUGGAGAUGCUCAGAAUCAAGAGCAUGGCGGAGUAGGAGAAGAAGCCCUGCACACAGGGCAGUGUCCACAGCCAGAAAACUCCUGCUGGGCACCAACCACUACGAGCAUACCCCAUGCCCACCGUGGAGCUGCAACUCCUCGACAGCACUGAGUUUGAUAGUCUCACUGGAAGCAGAUCAGCUGAUGUAGAACAGAGACCUCGGCCAUAAAGGUGAGAAGACAUAGGGAUUUCAACCACACAGUUGGGACAGAAGGGACAGUGCAUCUGUUCAUCCAUCCUGCACUUGGCCCACGUUGAACUCCAUGGUGCCUGAGAGAGACUAGUUAAGGGUUGGUCUUCUGUAUCCUCUGCUGUUGAGCCUCUGGUAAGCUUUCAUCUCCCAUGAACUCAUUUCCCCAUAAAUGAAAUGGGUAAAUAAUGCCCCAUUUGUAGAAGUGGGCCCUCAUGACUGAGGUAGCUUCCAGAUAGGCCAGAGUAGAGUGUAGAGUGUGCCCCGUGACAUCCCUCCAUCUUCUCCUCCAUUAUCAUCUAGCAGGGUCAGACUGGGAAACCUGGUUGGCCACGCCACACCAUGACCGAGGAGCCAACUGGGACUUCUGGCUGUUUGACAUCCUCAUGUUCCCGUUGGUCUUCCGGAGAAUAGUGCUACCCUCACAUCCCCUGGAGCACAGCCUUCCUGAAAUGCCCUCACCCCAUGCCUUUGCCAUUGUGUGCUCUCAGAUUUCUUCCACUGUUUGACACCCUCCUUAGAGGGCUGCUCUUUUUUUUCCAGAGAUAAUCCUAGCCAUCCUCUCCACUCCCACGGCUGGGGACAAUGGCCACUUACUACCUGUGCACUUUGCCACUCGGGACACCUGGAUGGUUUCUCUUAGGACUUUGCCCACCUCCUUCUCAUGGCACUUGCUGUGGAAAAUGCCUGGCUGGCCUCGUGGGGCCUGUCUCACUUUUCCAGGAGACAUGACCCACUAACGUGGCAACUUUAACCCAAAGGCCCCUCAGACAUGUUACAGCAAAUCUGGAGCCACAGACAGGUUCCCUCCAUUGGCAGCCCAUUGUGUUUGAAAUUCCAUGUCGGGUUUACUUGGAAUGAAAGAUACUUGAAUUAUUGUGCGCCUGUGAGCGCCCAGCUUCUGUUUCAUAGUCUUAACAGGUGGCCAUUGUCGUGAAACGAGUGAUGCCUGAAGAUCUCAGUGAUGUUUGAACCUUCUGUGUAACUUUUUAUUAAGUCUUUGUAUCUCUCGACUGAUUAAUAAAGAAGAGAAACACGUA